AAACCUGCGAUCGCCACGGUCCUUCCGCCCUCUCCUUCGUCCGCUCCAUGCCCAAGAGCUGCGCUCCGGAGCUGGGGCGAGGAGAGCCAUGGAGGAACCGGGUGCUCAGUGCGCUCCACCGCCGCCCGCGGGCUCCGAGACCUGGGUUCCUCAAGCCAACUUAUCCUCUGCUCCCUCCCAAAACUGCAGCGCCAAGGACUACAUUUACCAGGACUCCAUCUCCCUACCCUGGAAAGUACUGCUGGUUAUGCUAUUGGCGCUCAUCACCUUGGCCACCACGCUCUCCAAUGCCUUUGUGAUUGCCACAGUGUACCGGACCCGGAAACUGCACACCCCGGCUAACUACCUGAUCGCCUCUCUGGCGGUCACCGACCUGCUUGUGUCCAUCCUGGUGAUGCCCAUCAGCACCAUGUACACUGUCACCGGCCGCUGGACACUGGGCCAGGUGGUCUGUGACUUCUGGCUGUCGUCGGACAUCACUUGUUGCACUGCCUCCAUCCUGCACCUCUGUGUCAUCGCCCUGGACCGCUACUGGGCCAUCACGGACGCCGUGGAGUACUCAGCUAAAAGGACUCCCAAGAGGGCGGCGGUCAUGAUCGCGCUGGUGUGGGUCUUCUCCAUCUCUAUCUCGCUGCCGCCCUUCUUCUGGCGUCAGGCUAAGGCCGAAGAGGAGGUGUCGGAAUGCGUGGUGAACACCGACCACAUCCUCUACACGGUCUACUCCACGGUGGGUGCUUUCUACUUCCCCACCCUGCUCCUCAUCGCCCUCUAUGGCCGCAUCUACGUAGAAGCCCGCUCCCGGAUUUUGAAACAGACGCCCAACAGGACCGGCAAGCGCUUGACCCGAGCCCAGCUGAUAACCGACUCCCCCGGGUCCACGUCCUCGGUCACCUCUAUUAACUCGCGGGUUCCCGACGUGCCCAGCGAAUCCGGAUCUCCUGUGUAUGUGAACCAAGUCAAAGUGCGAGUCUCCGACGCCCUGCUGGAAAAGAAGAAACUCAUGGCCGCUAGGGAGCGCAAAGCCACCAAGACCCUAGGGAUCAUUUUGGGAGCCUUUAUUGUGUGUUGGCUACCCUUCUUCAUCAUCUCCCUAGUGAUGCCUAUCUGCAAAGAUGCCUGCUGGUUCCACCUAGCCAUCUUUGACUUCUUCACAUGGCUGGGCUAUCUCAACUCCCUCAUCAACCCCAUAAUCUAUACCAUGUCCAAUGAGGACUUUAAACAAGCAUUCCAUAAACUGAUACGUUUUAAGUGCACAAGUUGACUUGCCGUUUGCAGUGGGGUCGCCUAAGCGACCUUUGGGGACCAAGUUGUGUCUGGUUCCACAGGUAGGUCGAAUCUUCUUUCGCGGUUUCUGGGUCCCAGCGAGGCUCUCUCUCCUGGGCAAGGGCAAUGGAUCCUGAGAAGCCAGAAUAGUCCUGAGAGAGAGCUCUGAAAGGAGAAGUGUUGAAACUAAAUGUAGAGCUUCCCUGCCCAGGAGGAGGCUCACUUCCUCCCCUCAAGCCCCGGGCUCAGCACUGACCCUGCGGCAGCCAAUCCCAAAGGGGGUUGCAACUUUUAAAAAUUGAUAAUGGAAGGGAAUCCCUGCCCUGCUUUGGUAUCGUGGAUAAUGCCCACUAGAAGCAGUGUACUUGUAAUUGUUGUCUGAAGCCUGUCUGAGACAGAUCUACAUACAGCCUGGCAGUACUUGAACUAGACGCUUAAUGCCCUGUGUUUUUGGGGGGAGAACUUUGUGUUACAGCUUAAUUUAAGAACAGUUACUUUGGCAUCAUUCAGUCUUCACUUUUUGUCUAUUUAAACUUGGUUGGAGAAACUUGUGGAUUUGGUGCUUCAAACCCUAUGUGUGGCUUGGAUGGCGCAGAGAAACCUUGAAGAGUUAACAGCAAAAUUCUGAUGCUGAGAUCUCUAUUUUUAUUAUACUUGAAACUAUAUGGGGGUGGGUGGGUGGGAAUGGGAGAUGAGGAGUGUUAAACUGAGAAUCAACACCUAUGAUUGUUUGUUUUCUGCAGAUUUACAAUUUUGUAAUUCCUGUUUAGCGAUUGUCAAGCCACAACUCUAACAAACAAACCAUUAUGUGUGCUAGUGCCGAAGUCUGCAGACUGCUUUAUUUUUUCUCUUAAUUUCAUGUACCUGUCACUUUACACAUUUAAAUCCCCAUAAAUGAAGGGUAUGAUGGGUGACUCAGCCCACACUGCUGCUAUAUUUCUUACUAAUGCAAUUGGUAAAACCGAUUAGUAUUGGAAAUAUACUGUUUCUUAACAAGAAAAGUGUCUUUAUUUCUUAUCCAAUUUAGUGAGAUGUGAAGGAGACUGAUGACAUGGGGAUAGUUCUUACACAAUUGAGGAAUGGGGUGGGGGCAAUAGGAGGAUGUAUAUUUUGACUUGUAAAAAAAUCUUAAAAUGCAUGAAACUUUUAUCUGAUAGUCAUUUGCACUCUCCUUCCCAUCUGUGAUUCCUUGUGUGCUAACAUAUAAAGAAACCAAGAGAACUAUCUUCCUUCUCCAGAAACCUUAAAAAUACAGUUAAGGGCCCUAAAAACGAUAUUGAAAAGAAAAUAAACUUGUUUCUUUUU